GUUGUUGUGGCUCCGAGGGCUGUUCGAGGAGCUGCUGCUGCUGAGGCGGCGGCAACUGCAUUGAGGUGGUGGCGGCGCUGCCGGCCCCGGGCCGCUCGGCCUCUCGGCUCGCCUUCCAGCCUCGCCUGAGCCCGCCGGGGCCCGCGCCGGCCAGCGCCUGCCCUAUGAGUGUGUCACUGGUUGUUAUCCGAUUGGAGCUCGCGGAACACUCGCCUGUCCCCGCCGGCUUCGGCUUCAGCGCCGCGGGUGAGUCCCGCGGCCUCGCCGCAUUCCCUGUAGCCGGGUCUGGGCCCGGAGGGCUUCCCUUCCCAAAGCACUGGCCCGGGAAAAGCCCGCGGCGAGGGCUGUUGCCCAGGAAGACACGGAGAGCCGGGGAAAUGUCUGAUGAGGAGAUAAAAAAGACGACACUAGCCUCAGCUGUAGCCUGUUUAGAAGGCAAGUCACCAGGAGAGAAAGUAGCGAUUAUCCAUCAGCAUCUCGGCCGUCGAGAAAUGACAGAUGUGAUCAUUGAGACCAUGAAGUCCAACCCAGAUGAACUAAAAACUACAGUGGAAGAAAGGAAGUCUUCAGAAGCCUCCCCCACUGCGCAAAGAAGUAAAGAUCACAGUAAGGAAUGCAUAAACGCUGCCCCAGAUUCUCCGUCCAAACAGCUUCCAGACCAGAUUUCAUUCUUCAGUGGAAAUCCAUCAGUUGAAAUAGUUCAUGGUAUUAUGCACCUAUAUAAGACAAAUAAGAUGACCUCCUUAAAAGAAGAUGUGCGGCGCAGUGCCAUGCUGUGUAUUCUCACAGUCCCUGCUGCAAUGACCAGUCAUGACCUUAUGAAGUUUGUUGCCCCAUUUAACGAAGUAAUUGAACAAAUGAAAAUUAUCAGAGACUCUACUCCCAACCAAUAUAUGGUGCUGAUAAAGUUUCGUGCACAGGCUGAUGCGGAUAGUUUUUAUAUGACAUGCAAUGGCCGCCAGUUCAACUCAAUAGAAGAUGACGUUUGCCAGCUAGUGUAUGUGGAAAGAGCUGAAGUGCUCAAAUCUGAAGAUGGCGCCAGCCUCCCAGUGAUGGACCUGACUGAACUCCCCAAGUGCACGGUGUGUCUGGAGCGCAUGGACGAGUCUGUGAAUGGCAUCCUCACAACGUUAUGUAACCACAGCUUCCACAGCCAGUGUCUACAGCGCUGGGACGAUACCACGUGUCCUGUUUGCCGGUACUGUCAAACGCCCGAGCCAGUAGAAGAAAAUAAGUGUUUUGAGUGUGGUGUUCAGGAAAAUCUUUGGAUUUGUUUAAUAUGCGGCCACAUAGGAUGUGGACGGUAUGUCAGUCGACAUGCUUAUAAGCACUUUGAGGAAACGCAGCACACGUAUGCCAUGCAGCUUACCAACCAUCGAGUCUGGGACUAUGCUGGAGAUAACUAUGUUCAUCGACUGGUUGCAAGUAAAACAGAUGGAAAAAUAGUACAGUAUGAAUGUGAGGGGGAUACUUGCCAGGAAGAGAAAAUAGAUGCCUUACAGUUAGAGUAUUCAUAUUUACUAACAAGCCAGCUGGAAUCUCAGCGAAUCUACUGGGAAAACAAGAUAGUUCGGAUAGAGAAGGACACAGCAGAGGAAAUUAACAACAUGAAGACCAAGUUUAAAGAAACAAUUGAGAAGUGUGAUAAUCUAGAGCACAAACUAAAUGAUCUCCUAAAAGAAAAGCAGUCUGUGGAAAGAAAGUGCACUCAGCUAAACACAAAAGUGGCCAAACUCACCAACGAGCUCAAAGAGGAGCAGGAAAUGAACAAGUGUUUGCGAGCCAACCAAGUCCUCCUGCAGAACAAGCUAAAAGAGGAGGAGAGGGUGCUGAAGGAGACCUGUGACCAAAAAGAUCUGCAGAUCACCGAGAUCCAGGAGCAGCUGCGUGACGUCAUGUUCUACCUGGAGACACAGCAGAAGAUCAACCAUCUGCCUGCCGAGACCCGGCAGGAAAUCCAGGAGGGACAGAUCAACAUCGCCAUGGCCUCGGCCUCGAGCCCUGCCUCUUCGGGGGGCAGUGGGAAGUUGCCCUCCAGGAAGGGCCGCAGCAAGAGGGGCAAGUGACCUUCAGAGCAACAGACAUCCCUGAGACUGUUCUCCCUGACACUGUGAGAGUGUGCUGGGACCUUCAGCUAAAUGUGAGGGUGGGCCCUAAUAAGUACAAGUGAGGAUCAAGCCACAGUUGUUUGGCUCUUUCAUUUGCUAGUGUGUGAUGUAGUGAAUGUAAAGGGUGCUGACUGGAGAGCUGAUAGAAAGGCGCUGCGUUCGAAAAGGUCUUAAGAGUUCACUAACCUCACAUUCUAAUGACCAUUUUGCCUUCCUGCUUGGUAGAAGCCCCAACUCUGCUGUGCAUUUUUCCAUUGUAUUUAUGGAGUUGGCGUAUUUGACAUUCAGUUCUGGGGUAGGUUUAAGAUGUUAAGUUAUUUCUUGUAACCUCAAAGGUAAGGUUAUCUAGCACUAAAGCACCAAACCUCUCUGAGGGCAUAACAGCUGCUUUAAAGAGAGGUUUCCAUUGGCUAUUAAGGAGUUAUGAAAACUCCCUAGCAAUAGUGUCAUAUCAUUAUCAUCUCCCCCUUCCUCUGGGGAGUGGAAGAAUUGCUUGAAUGUUAUCUGAAAAGAGGCCUGGUAGUAAACCAGGCCCUGGCUCUUUACCAGCAGUCAUCUCUUCUUGCUCUGGGGCCAGCCAGGAAAAACAAACAACCCGGGGCACAUUGGGUAGACUCAGUGUAGGAAAAAUGGUGGCAGCUCCACUGUUUAUUUUUGGUGACUUCGUACAUCAUUAUGAACCGCAAUUAAGGAGGAGGCUUAAUGGCUGUUCCCAAACUCAAAUCUCAGAGUGGGUAUCCUAGCAUCUAGCAAGACUGAGUGGGGAGAUUUCUCAUCCGUGUGAAAAUGUAGAGUGAGGCCUCUGACUAGCUAAUUGUGUAUUUUGUUGGGUUUAGUAUUUUCUAAAUGUUUACAAAAUAUUGGGCUGCAUGUUCAGGUUGCAGCUAGAGGGAGCUUGGGCAGAUUUUCAAUUACGCUUUCAAGAUAUAACCAAAAGCUGUUUCUAAAUCCUAAAAUUAGAAUUUCAACAGAGCCCCCUUUAGAACAGUCAUAUAACGCUUGUGUGGGCCAACAGAGGGGCUGUGUACUCUCUCUGGAACCAUAAAUGUCAAAUAAUUUAUAACCUGCAGUAAUUGAGCAAACUUAAAAUAAGACCUGUGUUGGAAUUUAGUUUCUUGAAGAGGUAGAGGGAUAGGUUAGUAAGAUGUAUUGUUAAACAACAGGUUUUAGUUUUUGCUUUAUAAUUAGCCACAGGUUUUCAAAUGAUCACAUUUCAGAAUAGGUUUUUAGCCUGUAAUUAGGCCUCAUCCCCUUUGACCUAAAUGUCUUACAUGUUACUUGUUAGCACAUCAACUGUAUCACUAAUCACCAUCUGUUUUUGUGGGAUGUGCUGCAGCAUUUCCCAAAAAACUUUACGUGUAAUGUUGCAAAAUGAAUGUACUCAGACAUUCUUAAUUUUUACUUAGGGCAGACCAACUCUUUGAGUCUCUCUUGGACUUAUAUAUACAGAUAUCUUAAGAGUGGGAAUGUAAAGCAUAACCUAAUUCUCUUUCCUAUAGAGAUUCUAUUUUAUUUAAAAUCUAUUUUUACACUAGUUAGAAUCCUGCUGUUUUGGCCAAGUACUUGUCUUGCAUGUCUGACCUUGCAGAAGCUGGGGUGGAUCAUAGCAUACUAAUGAAGAGAAUUAGAAGUAGUUUACAAAGCUCGCUCACUCCUCAUUUCUCUGUGAUCCCUUCUAUCCAGUGGCCCCACCACCACCUGGGAAAACAGAUUUUUCAGUACAGGUGGGAUAAAUGCUCUGAAAGGCUGUGCCCAGAGGAAUGAGCAAAUAGGCAAGUGUUUCCAAACUACUUGGAGGUUUACAAAAAAUAUGUCCCAGAAAAAAAAAAAAUCUUACCAAGAUACGUAAAGAAAAAAAAAUUUUUUUUUAAACAGUCAAAGAGUCAUGUUUGAAUUUCACAAAAUCACAUCAGACAGAAGUUGUUUUCUUCAGGAGGGAAAUGAACCACUUAAUAUACCCAUACUACCUUGAACAAUGAAAUUGAAUUAAAAUAGCCAAACUUUGAAAUUA